AGACCUGGCUCGGGGUGGGAGUGCAGAGGCAACCAAAAAGGAACCCACACCUCCCUCCAGGGCCCGGGGCGCUGUCAGACGGGGCAGCAACCAGGAGAUUCCCUGGGCCUGCAGGAAGCCCUUCCGCGGACCGAAAGAUUGUUCCCCAUUUUGGAGAUGAAGAAACUGAGACUCAAAGCAGCUGAGUGACCUUCCCAAGGACACACACUGAACUGCCCUCUGGGGUGGAAGCUGCCAUCCAAAGCCUGGCAAAUCUGAAGUCCACCACACUGAACAUUCCACAGAGACUGGGCGGUGAUCAGGAUCUGAAUGCACAGGGCGGGUGUUCAGCGAUUGUUUACUACGUUGAACGUGACCUCCAGGAAAGCAGUUCUGGCCGAGAUCCCCUGACAACGCAAAGCAAGAAGUAACGUGGAAGGAGGCUCCCCAAGCUGGCUGGCCAUUUUGCUGCUGUGUGUGGAGGUGCUGCCAGUGGCAUGCCCAAACCCAAAGCUGGAAGAGGAAUAAAUUACAAGUGGUCAAGGUUGCAUCCUUUUGAGCCCAGGACCUGCUUGUAAGCCGAGAGGGUUCUCUGGCCCUAAUCUAGCCAAGCACCAUGGAGAGAAUCAGUGCCUUCUUCAGCUCUAUCUGGGACACCAUCUUGACCAAACACCAAGAAGGCAUCUACAACACCAUCUGCCUGGGAGUCCUCCUGGGCCUGCCACUCUUGGUGAUCAUCACACUCCUCUUCAUCUGUUGCCAUUGCUGCUGGAGCCCACCAGGCAAGAGGGGCCAGCAGCCAGAGAAGAACAAGAAGAAGAAGAAGAAGAAGAAGAAGAAGGAUGAAGAAGACCUCUGGAUCUCUGCUCAACCCAAGCUUCUCCAGAUGGAGAAGAGACCAUCACUGCCUGUUUAGUUAGGCAGGAAGCAGAGGUGUUUCCUUUCUGGGGCUAAGCCUCCUUCUGACCACACACAGACAUUUCAGGAACCCCUGAAAUAAUGCACUAUGUCCAUGUCCACAGAGUAACUACUCAACCAAGGAACAAACCUCAGACUAAGUGUCCCAGUGGAGGGCAGUCCCAGGGACCACGUGGACAAUUCUUGGAUACUGUCUUGGCAGCUAUGUGUCCAAUAGCAAUGCUCCUUACUGCAGACCCAGGCAUGCCUCCCACCUGUCUCUGGCAUACCCCACAUGCAAAGCACAAAGAACAUUUAUCCAUACAUCUCAAUAUGGUUCCCAAGUGUGUGCACAUGCACGUAACACACACACACACAAAUUCAGGUAGCAGGUACGUGGGCAAGUAUAUUCUGCUCAUCAAAUGGUCAUUGGCUAUGUACUUUGUGCAGGGAAGUACAUUAUCUACAGUCACAAAAAUGUCUCAUGGGAAAGCCUUGCCAGAUUCAGACACAUAUAUACAAUUUCCUAACCAGCAAGGCCCCCAUACACCAUCUAUUCCAUAAACCACUCAGGUUACAGAUGCAUGCUUUCCUAUUUCUAACUCUACACAUAAACUUUUACUGGAAGUACUCAUAAUUGGACAUUCCAGCAACCUGCUACAGUCCCCACCCUUGUGUGUCUUGAUACAGACACACCAAGUUUCUGUGCCUCUGACCCCUCACCUGUGCCAAGAUGUUUAAAGUGUGAUGGUUCAAAAUUCAUUGAAAGCUCUUUUCUUGUAACUCAUGACAAAGUCCGUCCUCAUUGCCACUGAGAGGUGUUUAAUGUGAUCCAAGACCUCUCUGUGAAACAUUACCCCCGCAAACCACUCAGCAAAGUGCCUUUCUCCAAGCAAGAACAAAGAGCUCUUGGUGGUGACUGCUAGAAAAUUAUGGAAGCCCACUCAUUUAUGUCAGUGGACUGCAACUGUGUACCUGUGCAAUGUUUACAGAUGGAAAGGGUGAGGAGAUGCUACACCUGAGCUAGGUAUCUCCUAUAUAACCAAAGUUUCCAGCAGGGAAGGAACUAGACAAUCAUCAGUGCAGUCUCACAGAAGGCAACACUGGAAGUGAUGUCAUAAGGUUGUGAUGUGUGCACGGUAUGGCACAGGUGGGAUGCAGAGGUAACAGAGUUUAAAUGAAAGUAGGAUGAAGCUAUAAAGAGGUUUAUUUAUAUUUAUAUUGAAGCUCAGGCAAGUGCCUUGCACACAGUAGGUACUUAUAACUAACUGUGGUUACUGUUGGAUAUGUGAUGUUGUUAAGGGUAAGCUUGUAAUACCUCACCAGUUCUCCCCGAGUGAUCUUCUCUUCUAAGUGAGCCCACUAAUUGCUGCAAUGGAUGAAAUUGGGUGUUUAAUGCUGGAGAGCACAUGUAGGUGACACAUGUGCCUUGAGGUAUGUGAGGACAUGUAAAUUAGAUCCACAGUGAGCUGAGGAGGGCUUUCCCCGCCAGAGUGAGGUUGGGAAGCAGAGUUAAUCCACUUAUAGGAUGAACUGCUUGGUAUUUUUAUUGUAUUGUGACUGUAUUACAAAGAUGGACAAUUCACUCCUUGGGAGCAAGUUAUGCUCUAGAAGUUUAUUUACAAAUAUGCUGGGCAGCUCUCUUGAAAUAUUUUCCCAAGGAAGCUAUUCUACACAGUGGCAAAAUUGCUAUCUAAUUAAUAAUGUAGCUAAACUAUGAUAUUUAUAGUAGCAAAAAACUAAAUUCUAUAAGAUUGCAUUAAAGGAAAGAUAUAUUCUAUUUGCUCACUUGGGCUGCUUGGUACUCACCUGCCCUCCAGGUGUACUUUAGGCCUGUGGAGGGUGGGCAUUUAGUGGUGACCCUUGCACCAGGGUUUUCUAACAGAUGACCCUGUGAAUCAUAAUUUAAACCUGCAUAUAUUUUAUAGCCAGUCACAUUUGCCCUCUCACCCUAUAUGGCCAUAAACUGCCUAAGCACUCAGGCCUCCCACUCAUCAACCCCUUUGACCAGAGAAAGAAGCACUCUGGUUCUCUAUCCCCUUGUCACAUAGAGAGUUUGUCAUGGGGCCUCUGGCUGUGCCCUUCACAUAACAGAAUGACUUGCCAUCUGCCUGCACCAAACCCAGGGAUGUGGAAGACAUCUCCCCACAACUGCCACUGCUCACCAGGACAAGCUGCCCUUCCUGUCUCCACCUCUCAGUCCCCCUAGAAUGGAUGGCUGGGGAGAGGUGGAGGCUGACAGCUGAGACGUAGUGUCAGAUAUGAUCUAGGAGGGCGGAUCACCGGGAUCCGGGACCAUACAAGUAACAUGGUUUCCAUGGCAACUGCUUGCUCCUUUGAAUUAAGACAGCAGUCAGUUGUCAUUGCCAUGACAAGGCCUCUAUCUCCAGGCACAAUGUCCCUGCUGUCUCCUAAUCCAAUGGACUUGCUCUCACCCCAGGGAUGAAACACCCAGAAACUCACUUCUCAGUCACUUCCACAGCCGAUGACUCAGAAGAGCCAAACCCAGAAUGGGGCCUCUCUUUUCCCCAUCACAGACUCCCCUGACAACCUUUCCUGGCGUAACUAGAGGAGUCCCAGUGCAGGAUAGGCCCUAAACGUUUUGUUAAAUAAACAGGUGCAUGAAAGGAGCCUAAGGCCAUUGUUGAUAUCCACUCUCUUCUUUCCACUUCCUUCUCAUCUUUUUCUCCAUGUUUUAUGCUUCUCUGAUUCCCUCUUCUGCCUGCACCAGACCAGCCCCAGCCCUUUAUUCCUCUCCAUUUUCACUCCUUCCAGCCUCUGUCCCUGAACUGCCACUGGCAACCCAUGGGACCUCAGGACCAGAGACUGCUUGACUCAUCUGGGGAGGGUAAGUUCACGGGGGACAAAAAAAUGAUUCCUAAAGAAGAGGCUUCCUAGACCAGCACAGGCUCGAGAAAGACAUCCCCUAGGCCUGGACUUCUGAGCAGCUUUAGCCAGGCUCCGGACGGCAGCCAGAGGAGGCCUUUCCCCAUUGCUCCUUUCCCCAUUGCUCAAUGGAUUCCAUGUUUCUUUUUCUUGGGGGGAGCAGGGAGGGAGAAAGGUAGAAAAAUGGCAGCCACCUUUCCAAGAAAAAUAUAAAGGGUCCAAGCUGUAUAGUAUUUGUCAGUAUUUUUUUCUGUAAAAUUCAAACACACACAAAAGAAAAAUUUAUUUAAAUAAAAUACUUUGAAAAUGAAAAGUCUUGAUGUAGUCAGAUGGUUACUCUCUUAACAUUAGGUAUUACCCCCACUCAGACAUCACUCAGAAAUGAUCAAUGCAGGGACUCUUUCUGUGACACAAAUGUCCCAGCCCUCCCUGGUCACCGCCUUCGCCAUGGUAGAGUCAUAGGUCUGAGGAUGAGGAAUGUGGCUGUCUCACCCUUGCUUGCAAAACAGAUGGCCUUGGAGACCAGACUCCCUCAAAGGUGCCAGCUACAGGAAAAAUAUACUGAUGUUCCUUGGCAACACUUACAGAACUUUCCAUCAAUGAGGUCCAUCAAUGGCUUCUUAAAGGAAAAGGGGGGAAAUAGCAAAAACCUAAGGAAGAAUGGACCUUUGAGUUAAAUCCAGUGUUUGUUGGGAAAGGAGGGAUCAAAAACCUCUAUAGUAGCCACUAGGGCAAAAACUGUGUGUAUGUGUGUGUGUAAGUGUGUGUACACUGUUCAAUAUGGUUCAAUAUGGUACCAAUAGCCACAUGUGACUAUUUAAAUUCAUUGCAAUGAAAUAAAAUUAAAGGUAUACUAGCUCA